AUUCACUCUGUCUUGCUGCCCUGUGAAGAAAGUACCUUUCUUCCCCUUUCUUCCCCUUCAUCUCCUGCCAUGACUAUAAGUUUCCUGAGGCCUUCCCAGCCAUGCAGAACUGUGAGUCAAUUAAACUCCUUUUCUUUAUAAAUUACCCAGUCUUGGGUAUUUCUUCAUAGCAGCAUGAGUACGGACUAAUAUGGUAUCUCAUACUUUUUUCUAACUUUUUAUUUUGAAAUAAUUAUAGAUUCACCAGAAGUUGCAAAGAUAAUAUAGAGAGGUCCUAGGUACCCUUCAUCUAGUUUAUCUUACAUAAUUAUAGUACAAUAUCAAAAUCAAGAAUUUGACAUUGGUACUAUGCAUAUAUAUGUCUUUGUGUCAUUUAUCAUAUGCGUACAUUUGCGCAAAAACUACCACAAUAAAGAUACAGAACUGUUCCACCUUAAAGAUCAUUCCCAUACUUCUCCUUUUUAUGCACUCAUACCACUCCUAAUCAUCUCUAACCCCUGACAACCACUAAUCCGUUCCAUCUUUGUAAUUUUGUCAUUUUGAGAAUGUUCUAUAAAUGGAAUUAUAUCCUUUAGACCUUUCUGACUCAGCAUAAUGCCCUUGCGAUCCAUCCAAGUAUGCAUCAAUAGUUUGAGUCUUUUUAUUGCUAAGUACUAUUCCAUGGUAUGGAUGUAUGAAAGUUUAUUUAGUCAUUCAUCGAUUGAGGGUUAUUUUAGUUGUUUCCAGUUUUUGGUUUUACAAAUAAAUCUUCUAUGAAUAAUUGUGUACAAGUUUUUCUCUUUAAGAGGCGGGGUCCCUCUAUGUUGCCCAGGCUAGCCUCAUACUUCUGGCCCCAAGGGAUCCUCCUACCUUUGCCUCCCAAAGCACUUGUACAGGUUUUUGUGUGAACACAGUAUUUAUUUCACUGGGACAAAUGUUCACAAGUGUCAUUGCUGCGUCAUAUGGUAGUUGCAUGUUUAGUCCUUAAGAAAUUGCCAAAUUGUUUUUCAAAGUGGCUAUACCAUUUUAUACUCCUACCAGCAAUAUAUGAGUGAUAGAUGUUCUCUGUAUCAUGGCCAUCAUUUGGUAUUGUCACUAUAUUUUAGCUGUCCUGAUAGGUGUAUGGUAAUAUCUCAUUGUGGUUUUAAUUUGCAUGUCUCCAAUGACUAAUGAUGUUAAACAUUUUUUUGUGUGCUUAUUUGCCAUCUGUAUAUCAGUCAGUGAAAUGUCUCUUCACGUCUUUUCUUAUUUUCUAAUAGAUUUUAUUUUUUACUGUUGAAUUCUGGAAGUUCUUUAUAUAUUCUAGAUCUAAGUCUUUUGUGAGAUAUAUAUGGUUUGCAAAUAUGUUCUCCCAGCCUAUAGCUUGUCUUUUCAUCAUCUUAGUAAGGUCUUUCAGAGAAUAAAAGUUUUAAAUAAAAGUUUUACUUUAAUUUUGAUGAAGUCCAAUUUGUCUAUUUUUUAAUGGAUCAUGCUGUUGGUGUCAUGCCUGAGAACUCUUCACCAAGCCCUAGGUUCUGCAGAUUUUCUAUGUUGUCUUCCGAAAGUGUUUUACAUUUAAAUCUAUAAUCCACUUUGAGAUGAUUUUUUAAGAUGUUAUGUUUAGGUUGAGGUUAAUUCUUUUGCCUAUGGAUAUCCAUUUUUUCCAGCAUCAUUUGUUGAAAAGAGUAUCCUCCCACUAUUGAAUUGCUUUUGCACCUUUGUCAAAAAUCAGUUGGCCCCACUAUUACUGGAUUCUCUAUUCUGUUCCAUCAACAUAGGUGUUGAUUCCUGUGCCAGUACUACAUAGUCUUGCUUACUGCAGCUAUACAAUAAGUCUUGAAAUUGUCUUUUUUUAGAAUUGUUUUAACUAUUUUAGUUCCUUUGCCUUUCUUUAUAUAUUUUAUGAUAUUCUUAUAUAUAGCUACUAAAAAUCUUAUUAGGAUUUUGAUAGGACCUAUGUUAAACCUUUAUGUAAAUUUAGGGAGAAUUGCUAGCUUUGCUAUCCUUAAUAUUCCAUUCUAUGAGCAUUAAAUGUCCAUUUAUUUAGAUCUUUGAUUUCAUCAGAAUUUUAUCAUUUUUAGCAUACAAAUCCUACACAUUUUGUUAGAUUCACACUUAAAUAUUUAAGUUUAUUUCAGAAAUAGUAAAUGGUAUUAUAUGUUUAAUUUUGGUUUUCUACAUGUCUGUUGCUACUAUAUAGAAAUGCUGCUUUGUAUGUUGAUCUUGUAUCCUGUUCUCUUGCUGAACUCAUGAGAUCUAGAGCUUUGUGUGUUUUAUUUUGUAGAGCCCUUGGAAUUGUCUACAUAGAUCAUCAUGUUGUCAACAAACGGAGACAGUUUUAUUUCUUCAAUUUCAAUCUAUCUGCCAUUUAUUUUCUUUUCCUGCCUGAUUGUGUUGGGUAAAACUUCCAGCACUGUGUUAAACAUGAGUGGGCCCUGUUAGCGUCCCAGCUGGAACCAACAUUUGCCAGGUAUGUUUUCCCUUGUUUUGAUGAGCCAGCUCUGAAGGCAACUUUUAAUAUUACAAUGAUUCAUCAUCCAAGUUAUGUGGCCCUUUCCAACAUGCCAAAGCUAGGUCAGUCUGAAAAAGAAGAUGUGAAUGGAAGCAAAUGGACUGUUACAACCUUUUCCACUACGCCCCACAUGCCAACUUACUUAGUCGCAUUUGUUAUAUGUGACUAUGACCACGUCAACAGAACAGAAAGGGGCAAGGAGAUACGCAUCUGGGCCCGGAAAGAUGCAAUUGCAAAUGGAAGUGCAGACUUUGCUUUGAACAUCACAGGUCCCAUCUUCUCUUUUCUGGAGGAUUUGUUUAAUAUCAGUUACUCUCUUCCAAAAACAGAUAUAAUUGCCUUGCCUAGUUUUGACAACCAUGCAAUGGAAAACUGGGGACUAAUGAUAUUUGAUGAAUCAGGAUUGUUGUUGGAACCAAAAGAUCAACUGACAGAAAAAAAGACUCUGAUCUCCUAUGUUGUCUCCCACGAGAUUGGACACCAGUGGUUUGGAAACUUGGUUACCAUGAAUUGGUGGAACAAUAUCUGGCUCAACGAGGGUUUUGCAUCUUAUUUUGAGUUUGAAGUAAUUAACUACUUUAAUCCUAAACUCCCAAGAAAUGAGAUCUUUUUUUCUAACAUUUUACAUAAUAUCCUCAGAGAAGAUCACGCCCUGGUGACUAGAGCUGUGGCCAUGAAGGUGGAAAAUUUCAAAACAAGUGAAAUACAGGAACUCUUUGACAUAUUUACUUACAGCAAGGGAGCGUCUAUGGCCCGGAUGCUUUCUUGUUUCUUGAAUGAGCAUUUAUUUGUCAGUGCACUCAAGUCAUAUUUGAAGACAUUUUCCUACUCAAACGCUGAGCAAGAUGAUCUAUGGAGGCAUUUUCAAAUGGCCAUAGAUGACCAGAGUACAGUUAUUUUGCCAGCAACAAUAAAAAACAUAAUGGACAGUUGGACACACCAGAGUGGUUUUCCAGUGAUCACUUUAAAUGUGUCUACUGGCGUCAUGAAACAGGAGCCAUUUUAUCUUGAAAACAUUAAAAAUCGGACUCUUCUAACCAGCAAUGACACAUGGAUUGUCCCUAUUCUUUGGAUAAAAAAUGGAACUACACAACCUUUAGUCUGGCUAGAUCAAAGCAGCAAAGUAUUCCCAGAAAUGCAAGUUUCAGAUUCUGACCAUGACUGGGUGAUUUUGAAUUUGAAUAUGACUGGAUAUUAUAGAGUUAAUUAUGAUAAAUUAGGUUGGAAGAAACUAAAUCAACAACUUGAAAAGGAUCCUAAGGCGAUUCCUGUUAUUCACAGACUGCAGUUGAUUGAUGAUGCCUUUUCCUUGUCUAAAAACAAUUAUAUUGAGAUUGAAACAGCACUUGAGUUAACCAAGUACCUUGCUGAAGAAGAUGAAAUUAUAGUAUGGCAUACAGUCUUGGUAAACUUGGUAACCAGGGAUCUUGUUUCUGAGGUGAACAUCUAUGAUAUAUACUCAUUAUUAAAGAGGUACCUAUUAAAGAGACUUAAUUUAAUAUGGAAUAUUUAUUCAACUAUAAUUCGUGAAAAUGUGUUGGCAUUACAAGAUGACUACUUAGCUCUAAUAUCACUGGAAAAACUUUUUGUAACUGCGUGUUGGUUGGGCCUUGAAGACUGCCUUCAGCUGUCAAAAGAACUUUUCGCAAAAUGGGUGGAUCAUCCAGAAAAUGAAAUACCUUAUCCAAUUAAAGAUGUGGUUUUAUGUUAUGGCAUUGCCUUGGGAAGUGAUAAAGAGUGGGACAUCUUGUUAAAUACUUACACUAAUACAACAAACAAAGAAGAAAAGAUUCAACUUGCUUAUGCAAUGAGCUGCAGCAAAGACCCAUGGAUACUUAACAGAUAUAUGGAGUAUGCCAUCAGCACAUCUCCAUUCACUUCUAAUGAAACAAAUAUAAUUGAGGUUGUGGCUUCAUCUGAAGUUGGCCGGUAUGUCGCAAAAGACUUCUUAGUCAACAACUGGCAAGCUGUGAGUAAAAGGUAUGGAACACAAUCAUUGAUUAAUCUAAUAUAUACAAUAGGGAGAACCGUAACUACAGAUUUACAGAUUGUGGAGCUGCAGCAGUUUUUCAGUAACAUGUUGGAGGAACACCAGAGGAUCAGAGUUCAUGCCAACUUACAGACAAUAAAGAAUGAAAAUCUGAAAAACAAGAAGCUAAGUGCCAGGAUAGCUGCGUGGCUAAGGAGAAACACAUAGCUUGUGGCUAUCUUUCAGCACUCCUCUUGCAUAUUAUAAUGUAGUUUGUUCACAGUUUUGUCUUCCAAUACUUUGUGAGUCUGGAAAACCACACAUUUUAUUUGUAUUUCAGUCACAUUUAUUACUCAGAGUGCCAUUCUUCUCAUAUUGUCAUGUUUGGCCCUGAGGGUGGGUGAUUGCUGACAAUUUUGCCAAUGCUGCUGUAUUUCUGGGAAAGAUGUCACUUCAUGUUGGGUUAUAAUCCCACAGAAUUUACUUUAAAUGUCACGUAAAAACAAAUUCACCUAAGAUAGUCUUGCUUAUUUUGUUGCGAAGGCCAGUGGAAUAUAAAAAUCAAUGGCAUUAAUGAGGAGCACAUUCUUUGCUGAGGGAAAUAACAGUUUUUCCAGGCCCUAGGGUUUAUUUAGUUCAACAUUGAAGAUUGAAAAGACUAAUGAGAAGAUAACAUGACAAUAUAAAAAGACAGAAACUCAAAAAGUAUAUUCACUAGAAGACAGUGGAGCCAAAGAAAAGCAAGUUGAAAAAGAAAGAGGAGACAAUUUAACGAGCCCUAAAGGCAAGAAGUGUGUCUUCUCCUGCCCAUUUCUCUCUCCCACAGUACAUCCUGCAUUGAACCACGUGUUGCUGGUUACUAAACUUUAUGGUGUCACAAAAAGACAAAUGAUUGUAGGAUCCAUGGAAGUGCACUUAGGCUUGCUGUGGUGGAGGCCAUAGUGGAGAUGAAGGCUCUGCUCUGAAGCUCUUAAUUGUGUAUUCACCAGUGGGAUGGACACCCUUUCAGCCUAAGCGUACGAGUGAAAACAAUGAUGUCAAAAGACAAUAGCAAGUAUAGGCUACUAUUUAGGGCAAAAGGAAUCUUGAAAUGAAAGAAACAGAACUAAAAGGCUAACUGGAGCAUAAUCCUUACAGUUUUGCACUCAGGGGAUUAAGUUUGAAACAUAGUGUCUUUUGGCCAAAUUGAACCUACUUGUAAUGUGGACCAACUUACUUUACACAUUUUCAUCAGUCCCAAUGUAUGGAAUUAGCUUAGUUUUCUCAUGCUUGAUUAAAACAAGACAACUAAAGCUAAUCAUUCCUCUUCUAGACUUUGUGUAUAUGAUUUAAUCUUUUAUUUUUAUUUUUGUAGAAUGGGGGUAAAACUACAAAUCUCCUCCUCAGGGUGAUAUUUUUAAAGAUUAAGGAGUAUGACAUCAAUUAACAGUCUUUAAAGAUGUUACAUACGCUCAAAGCAAUGUGAUUAAGACUUUUUGCCUAUUUCUUGUAUAAGUUAAGGCAGCCAUAAAUGAAAAUACAAAACAAACGUUUGCUUUUGUAUUUGAUUCACAAGAGGAUUCUCCCUGAGUGUCAGGGGAGGCUGUGGGACUUCACCACGUGGACAAACGAAAGCACAGGCUACUCAGACUUGGCCACAGGUCAUAGGUCAGAGAAUUUUUUCUUCAAAUGUAGAAAUGUAAAUUUUCAGCAAUAAAAUAUCUGCAUGCCUACAAA